AACUCAUCUUGCCCUGACUGGGAAUCUUUCGGAGAUUGGAUUUCAGAGUAUUCCCCAACCUGAUCGGAUAUCACCUCCUCAAUGGAAGCUUCCCUAAUACCCUCUGAUGUUUCUAGAAGCAGGACACAUGGCUUGUGUCAUAAGUCUUGACCUGAUUAUCAUAGAUUGCCUCACCAAGUUUAGCAUACCCUGUCUGAGAGUGAUGCUGGCAAAUUAGUGAAUAAGAGGACUGUGGAAUUUAUUUGAUUGCUAAUCUUGUGUCAGGACAUGGUUAUUUUUUAAAAAAGAAGUGUCCUCUUUUGAUCUUAACUGUUUGAUAUCUCAGCCCUUGAGUGAGGCAGUUAUAUGCAAAGGAGAUGAGAAGGAUGAGAAAAGUGAGUACUUUUCCUUCAUAAAAGCCACAUGAAUUGAACAAGACUUCAGAAUUCAGAAGAACUACAUCAAGUUCUUGGGUCAUUUUUUUAACCCAUUCUCCAAGAAUUGAAAAAAUGACCUUGCAAAUAUGUGCAAGACUCUGGAAUCUUCCUUUGGCAGAUGAUGAAUGAGAUGAAUAUUUCCAGGUGCUUGCCUUCAGCACCAGCACAUGUACAUUCUAGUACUCUUGGCCUUGAUCCUACACUGAAUCUGAGGGUGCAAGGACUUUAGAUAGAGGCUCAGGACAGACUGGACCUGUAUGAACUUCUGAAUUGUAGCUAGCCUGGGCAGCCAGUUACUUGGAUCCCUCUGGGGCUUCUGGACAAACAACUCUUUUAUAGCCCAAGGUAGAUGGUCAGGGGCGACCAGAGAGAGCAAUAGAUUCGUUGACUUCAAGCUUAACAUGAGUUAGCAGUAUGGUGAGGCUUCCAGCAAAAUCAUUCCCAUGGUUUGGCAUGGACAUCGGUGGAACGCUGGUUAAAUUGGUGUAUUUCGAGCCGAAGGAUAUUACAGCCGAAGAGGAGCAAGAGGAAGUGGAGAACCUGAAGAGCAUCCGGAAGUAUUUGACUUCUAAUACUGCUUAUGGGAAAACUGGGAUCCGAGACGUCCACCUGGAACUGAAAAACCUGACCAUGUGUGGACGCAAAGGGAACCUGCACUUCAUCCGCUUUCCCAGCUGUGCUAUGCACAGGUUCAUUCAGAUGGGCAGCGAGAAGAACUUCUCUAGCCUUCACACCACCCUCUGUGCCACAGGAGGCGGGGCUUUCAAAUUCGAAGAGGACUUCAGAAUGAUUGCUGACCUGCAGCUGCAUAAACUGGAUGAACUGGACUGUCUGAUUCAGGGCCUGCUUUAUGUCGACUCUGUUGGCUUCAACGGCAAGCCAGAAUGUUACUAUUUUGAAAAUCCCACAAAUCCUGAAUUGUGUCAAAAAAAGCCGUACUGCCUUGAUAACCCAUACCCUAUGUUGCUGGUUAACAUGGGCUCAGGUGUCAGCAUUCUAGCCGUGUACUCCAAGGACAACUAUAAAAGAGUUACAGGGACCAGUCUUGGAGGUGGAACAUUCCUAGGCCUAUGUUGCUUGCUGACUGGUUGUGAGACCUUUGAAGAAGCUCUGGAAAUGGCAGCUAAAGGCGACAGCACCAAUGUUGAUAAACUGGUGAAGGACAUUUACGGAGGAGACUAUGAACGAUUUGGCCUUCAAGGAUCUGCUGUAGCAUCAAGCUUUGGCAACAUGAUGAGUAAAGAAAAGCGAGAUUCCAUCAGCAAGGAAGACCUCGCCCGGGCCACAUUGGUCACCAUCACCAACAACAUUGGCUCCAUUGCUCGGAUGUGCGCGUUGAAUGAGAACAUAGACAGAGUUGUGUUUGUUGGAAAUUUUCUCAGAAUCAAUAUGGUCUCCAUGAAGCUGCUGGCAUAUGCCAUGGAUUUUUGGUCCAAAGGACAACUGAAAGCUCUGUUUUUGGAACAUGAGGGUUAUUUUGGAGCCGUUGGGGCACUGUUGGAACUGUUCAAAAUGACUGAUGACAAGUAGAGACGAGCAGUGGAGGAAACAGCCUCCCAAAAGGACAGAGAACUAAAAAAUUGCUGCUGGAGAAGGUGAAAGUCGCUUUGGGACGGAAGCCAAGCCAUUAUGGCAGAUGAACCUGCUGGAUUUGUAAAUAAUUUAAAAUCCUUCCAGAUGAUCUUUUACUCUUAGGUUUUGAGCUAAUGAUUCAAAACGGGGGAAUAUAAAAGGUUUUUUUUCUGUAUACUGUAUUUUUUUAAAAAAAUGGUGCAGCGUGGCCAAACCUACCAAUUGUAUGCAUUAACUUUGAAAAGUUGUUUGAUGUUUAAGAAGGACCUGAUAUGUAAGCGCUGGUCAUUUUUCUUCUGGGGUUUACUGAUCAGUGUGGUGAUUUUAACUUCAUUUAGUAAUUACUCUAGGAGAUUUUACCUUGACUUAUAUUUUUCAUGACGUUUCAUGAUUUGCUGUUGGUUUCAAAUGAAACUACAAAUCUGGCAUGUUUUACUGUGAACACUUUUGUUAUUUGUUUUGUACCCUUUUUUGUCUUGUUUUUCUGUUUUAGUUGUCUUCUGAAAAAAGAGUCGUUCCCUCUGUUUCUGUCCUCAGAUGAUGUCCCUCCCCCUACCUGUAACCUUUCUUUGACAUAAUUGUUCAUAUCAAUGAAGGUGCUGACCAGCUCAAUACAAAGUUAAGCACAAGAUCUAAAGCUCUUGAAAAUGCCCGUGAAGAGAAGACUGAAUGUGUUAAUGAAUUUAAUGAGUCUGGCAAAAGUUGCAAAUUAUAUGCAAGUUUGUCCUAUCGCUUAUAAAUGUAGUGUUUCAUUGGAUUUAUUUUAUGCUAGGUUAUAUUAAGUUGAAAUAGUCUGUGAUUAAAUGUCCUCAUCCAUGCACAGAAUAUGAAUGGCAGCAAAUCUUUGUGCAAGAAAUUUGAAACUUAUUGGGAAAAGCCUCCCAGUAGAUUAAUUGUUCAUAUCAGGAGAUUUAGGGUAAGUCAUGGGUUGAGGUGUCAGAUAGUAAUAUCUAUUUGUUUUGUACAUGUAUAUAUCUAGGAACUUUGUAACAACACAUCUUUAAUAAUGUUAAAGGUUUUUUCAUUUUUAAUAUUUUAAACUAAAAACUGUACUUCAAUCUCAGUUUCUAAAAUUAAAAAUAAUUUAUACUGAUCUAUAUAUUUUUUCUUUUUGAAAGAUUUCAUUAAGACUGAUGGGUAACUUUCAAAUGAGGGUCAUGUACAAAUAUUGGGAUGCAUGAGAUCCCAUGAUCUUGUGUAUUGAGCUUAUUGUUGAAAGGGAUUUUUGAAGGACAGAACAAUUACUCCAUGAUGAAUCUUCCUUUCUCUGCCUUCUGAGCACCGUCUUUAAUUUCCAUAUCUUCAAGUCUUGAAGAAGUUGAUGUUAAUUGAAGAAUUCACUUGUCUGGUUGAAAUAAAGCCUGUUUCUGUUGUGAUGUUUUUAGUGUAUAUGUUAUUUUCAUUUCUUAAUUCUCAUGUUUAUAGUAUCUGCUUUGUACCAUGAAAUGACUGUCUGUUGUGUUUUUGCUACUCUACAUUUCAAAAUUGGAGGCUUUCCCAUGAGUGUGGUAUGGUCCAAAACACUGUCUUCAGGUGAAGCUGUAGCCCUAUGCAUAGAUUUUUAAAAUAGAGCUUUAUUGUUUCUAUACAAGUGACUCCUUAAUGCCAACUACCUCUGCUAUAUUUGGUAAUUCCAAAGGAGUUUCAAAAUUUGGUCAUCACAGAUACAUUUUACCAACUUCUAUCUGGCUUUAAAAAAAUUCAGACAGCUAAAGUGUUCUUGAAAAGGAUAAGUUAAAAAUCUACAUAUUAUUUAUAAUUAGUGCCUUUUGAUGGCCUCUUCUAUUCCUAUUCUCAUCUAUCAGGUAACAGCAGACCUUGAUUCCGCAGAUCAUGGUUCUACAAAGGAAAUCAGGGCAAGUUAGUGUGACUGUAUUUUUUUUAAUUAUCUGAAAUCACUUGAUCUCUCAUUACAAACAUUUAAAAUAUUGGUGUAGCUGAGAAAAUACAUUAUUCCAUUAUACAAAUAUCAGUUAAAUGUUGACUACAUAUAGCCAGCCUGUUUUUUACAAAAGAGAUCUUGUAGCCUGAGGAUUUUCACAUUCACUUGAAUUACAGAAACUUUUCUUAGAAUCAACAUCACAAAGAAACUGGGAAGACUAAAGAAUUUUGACCUUGUGCAAUAUGAAGUAAGAGCAUGGCUUUUUAUCGUGAGGCAGCUUCAGUCUGGGUCCAGCUUAGUCAGUUACCAGUUCAAAGAUAUGCUAAGCCUCUUUCUAAACCAUAGUUUCCUCACCUAUAAAAUGGGACAAAUAAUUGUUUUACAUACAUAUUUAAAGAGCUCAGCACAGGGGUUGACACAAAGUAAAUGCUUCAUUAAUGAUAGCUACAAUGAAAAAAUAAAUUAUUUAAACUAAUUUAUUAAAUCAGUAAUUCUUAACUUUCUGGAUUGUGGGAAACCCAUGUUAGUAUGGAGAUGUUUCACCAAUCUCCGUAUGCUAAUACAUAUCCACAGCUCCUUGUCCACACUUCCAAAAUCCCAUACUUAAGAAAUCUAUCUUGACAGCUCACUUGGCAGCAAAAGCUGACUUGAGCAUUAUUUCUCACAUGUAGUAGGGCUCUUCACAUGUUUUGUUGCAAAGCUCGUCAUGAGUUAGAUAACAGGAUACUGACUCUGACAGGGGUGUUAAGUAAUAAACGAUUUUGAAUUGGCUGGGUGUGGUGGCUCACGCCUGUAAUCCCAGCACUUUGGGAGGCCGAGGCAGGCGGAUCAUGAGGUCAGGAGAUCGAGACCAUCCUGGCUAAUACGGUGAAACCCCGUCUCUACUGAAAAUACAAAAAGCUAGGCAUGGUGGUGGGCACCUGUAGUCCCAGCUACUUGGGAGGCUGAGGCGGGAGAAUGGCGUGAACCUGGGAGGCAGAGCUUGCGGUGAGCCGAGAUCACACCAAUGCACUCCAGCCUGGGAGACAGAGUGAGACUGUCUCAAAAAAAUAAAAUAAAUAAAUAAAUAAAUGAUUCUGAAUUUUGAAACACAUCUGAUCCCGAGUUUUAGACAAAGGGAUUGUGGAAAUAUAGUUGUGUUCUUCACCUUAUGCAGUAUACAUGGAUUCAGAGUCUCUUUGUUGGGAACAAUUGUUAUAGGUAAUGUAUACUUGAUGUCGUUCAGUCAUAGAAGGAAUAUUAAGAAGUUACUCUGUGCCAGGAAGGAACUGGAGACUAAGAUGCAUAGGAUACAGCCCCUGCAGAGAAAGACAGCAAAAUCUCAAGCCAACAUCAGUCAUCAAGUGCCACAAGUGCCAUUCAAUCAUUUAUUCAUUCACAUUCACAGCAGUAAACAGAACAAAGAUCCACCAUCACAGAGCUUAUAUUCUAGAAGGGAAGACAGGUACAUUACUAAAUAUAUAAUGUUAGAUCAGUACUACAAAGAAAAAGUAAGCUGGUGUAAAGGCUAAAUAAGGGGUAGUUCUAUUCAGAAAAAUGAGAAGGGGAGGAAUAUCUCAGGGUGGUCUAAGACAGCCUUUCCUAGGAAGUGACCUUUGAGCAGAGAGUUGAAUGGAGGUGAGAACACAUUGUGUAAAUGUCUGAGAAAAUAUUUUUCACUCCUGGCAAAUGAAAAUAGGGAUUUGAGGAACUGCAAAGAGGCCAGUGUCUGGAGUUAAAAAUAGAAAGUGGUGGGAGAUGCAGUGUUGGGAGUAAACUUGAGCCAGGUCCUAUAAGAAAUCUGUGAGGGUAGUGGCCUCUACCCAGAAGAGAGGUUGGUCAUUUGUCUUCCAGAAGGUGCUAGAGAAGGUUUUGUGAAGUCUUAACCAAAGAAUAGGAAUCACUAAGUGGAGAGGAAGGGAGGGCUUUCCAAGCAGAGGGAGCUGGGUGAGCAGAAGCGCUGAGGGAAGAAACCACUUGGCUUAUUCAGGGACUGGAAGCUCUUUGCUAUAGCUGGAGCCUGGUUCAUGAGACAGAAACCAGGUAGUGAGAAAGAGGAAGCUGGCCCAACUGUGGAAGGACUUGUCUUCCAUGCUAACAUUGCGGACUUUUCCGUAGUCACUGUGGAGCCAUCAAAGAGUUUCAAGGAAAGUGAAACUAGAAAUAAUCAGGUUUCAAAGUGGUAAAGCAAAAUGCUCUGUUGAAGUAAAUGAGUAAACAAGUUACGUACUUUUGAAUACCUAACAUUAUUCCAUUUUUUUCCCUAUUGUGCCAGACCUCAUGCAGUAGCUACAGAGUGAACCAUGCUUUCGCUGUAAGUAGGAUGGCUAUAAAAAUUAUUGAGAACUUUCUCAGAGGACACAGGCUACUAAUAGCUACAGCCCCACUAUGAGUCUAUUCAUUGAGCAAGAAGGUUUCAAUACUGGGAGCAUCGUAAACUAUCACUCACAAGAAUUGUUAGAAAGCAGUUUUCCUCCCAGUGAUCAGAAGAUGACGCCACAUUUGUGAAAAAGAUUUCAUUAGUGUACAUCGUUUAUUAGGUCUACCAGCUGCCCAUUCUUUUGCUCAUCUGUUUAAUUUUUAAUAAAUAUCAAUGAUCUGAGAGGCAUUGGGUAGCACUGAGGAUGCAAUCCGAUGUGAACAAGACUUCAGGAGCUCUGCUUUCAUUAGGCUUACAUUUGGUUAAUGGAGAUAAACUUGAAGCAUAUAAACCAAUAAAUAAACAAGAAAAUAUCAGGGAGUGACAAUUGCUAUUAAGGAAAGAAACAGGGUGAUAGGAUAGAGAGGGAGGAGAGAGACUUCUUCAGUCAGAUGAUCAUAAAAUGCAAGUAUGAUUAAGUCAUGGCCUCAACUUUUAAGGAAUGAUGGGCUCACCUUGCUUUCAUUCUUGCCACCUCCUCAAUGAAAAUGAAAGAUGUUUUUGGGAAACUGAUAGCUAAUUUUCUUUUUCUUAGAAUAUUUGAUUUAGAUAAUAUGUAUUUAAAAUAAAGUUAUCACGUAAAAUAAUA